ACUGAGCCGCUAUUACCGCGAAAGGCCGGCCUGGCUGCGACAGCCUGGGUAAGAGGUGUAGGUCGGCUUGGUUUUCUGCUACCCGGAGCUGGGCAAGCGGGUGGGAGAACAGCGAAGACAGCGUGAGCCUGGGCCGUUGCCUCGAGGCUCUCGCCCGGCUUCUCUUGCCGACCCGCCACGUUUGUUUGGAUUUAAUCUUCAGGUUGCCGGCGCCCGCCCGCCCGCUGGCCUCGCGGUGUGAGAGGGAAGCACCCGUGCCUGUGGCUGGUGGCUGGCGCCUGGAGGGUCCGCACACCCGCCCGGCCGCGCCGCUUGCCCGCGGCAGCCGCGUCCCUGAACCGCGGAGUCGUGUUUGUGUUUGACCCGCGGGCGCCGGUGGCGCGCGGCCGAGGCCGGUGUCGGCGGGGCGGGGCGGUCGCGGCGGAGGCAGAGGAAGAGGGAGCGGGAGCUCUGCGAGGCCGGGCGCCGCCAUGGAACUGGGCCCGGAGCCCCCGCACCGCCGCCGCCUGCUCUUCGCCUGCAGCCCCCCUCCCGCGUCGCAGCCCGUCGUGAAGGCGCUAUUUGGCGCUUCAGCCGCCGGGGGACUGUCGCCUGUCACCAACCUGACCGUCACUAUGGACCAGCUGCAGGGUCUGGGCAGUGAUUAUGAGCAACCACUGGAGGUGAAGAACAACAGUAAUCUGCAGAGAAUGGGCUCCUCCGAGUCAACAGAUUCAGGUUUCUGUCUAGAUUCUCCUGGGCCAUUGGACAGUAAAGAAAACCUUGAAAAUCCUAUGAGAAGAAUACAUUCCCUACCUCAGAAGCUGUUGGGAUGUAGUCCAGCUCUGAAGAGGAGCCAUUCUGAUUCUCUUGACCAUGACAUCUUUCAGCUCAUCGACCCAGAUGAGAACAAGGAAAAUGAAGCCUUUGAGUUUAAGAAGCCAGUAAGACCUGUAUCUCGUGGCUGCCUGCACUCUCAUGGACUCCAGGAGGGUAAAGAUCUCUUCACACAGAGGCAGAACUCUGCCCCAGCUCGGAUGCUUUCCUCAAAUGAAAGAGAUAGCAGUGAACCAGGGAAUUUCAUUCCUCUUUUUACACCCCAGUCACCUGUGACAGCCACUUUGUCUGAUGAGGAUGAUGGCUUCGUGGACCUUCUCGAUGGAGAGAAUCUGAAGAAUGAGGAGGAGACCCCCUCGUGCAUGGCAAGCCUCUGGACAGCUCCUCUCGUCAUGAGAACUACAAACCUUGACAACCGAUGCAAGCUGUUUGACUCCCCUUCCCUGUGUAGCUCCAGCACUCGGUCAGUGUUGAAGAGACCAGAACGAUCUCAAGAGGAGUCUCCACCUGGAAGUACAAAGAGGAGGAAGAGCAUGUCUGGGGCCAGCCCCAAAGAGUCAACUAAUCCAGAGAAGGCCCAUGAGACUCUUCAUCAGUCUUUAUCCCUGGCAUCUUCCCCCAAAGGAACCAUUGAGAACAUUUUGGACAAUGACCCAAGGGACCUUAUAGGAGACUUCUCCAAGGGUUAUCUCUUUCAUACAGUUGCUGGGAAACAUCAGGAUUUAAAAUACAUCUCUCCAGAAAUUAUGGCAUCUGUUUUGAAUGGCAAGUUUGCCAACCUCAUUAAAGAGUUUGUUAUCAUCGACUGUCGAUACCCAUAUGAAUACGAGGGAGGCCACAUCAAGGGUGCAGUGAACUUGCACAUGGAAGAAGAGGUUGAAGACUUCUUAUUGAAGAAGCCCAUUGUACCUACUGAUGGCAAGCGUGUCAUUGUUGUGUUUCACUGCGAGUUUUCUUCUGAGAGAGGUCCCCGCAUGUGCCGGUAUGUGAGAGAGAGAGAUCGCCUGGGUAAUGAAUACCCCAAACUCCACUACCCUGAGCUGUAUGUCCUGAAGGGGGGAUACAAGGAGUUCUUUAUGAAAUGCCAGUCUUACUGUGAGCCCCCUAGCUACCGGCCCAUGCACCACGAGGACUUUAAAGAAGACCUGAAGAAGUUCCGCACCAAGAGCCGGACCUGGGCAGGGGAGAAGAGCAAGAGGGAGAUGUACAGUCGUCUGAAGAAGCUCUGAGGGCGGCAGGACCAGCCAGCAGCAGCCCAAGCUUCCCUCCAUCCCCCUUUACCCUCUUUGCUGCAGAGAAACUUAAGCAAAGGGGACAGCUGUGUGACAUUUGGAGAGGGGGCCUGGGACUUCCAUGCCUUAAACCUACCUCCCACACUCCCAAGGUUGGAGCCCAGGGCAUCUUGCUGGCUACGCCUCUUCUGUCCCUGUUAGACGUCCUCCGUCCAUAUCAGAACUGUGCCACAAUGCAGUUCUGAGCACCGUGUCAAGCUGCUCUGAGCCACAGUGGGAUGAACCAGCCGGGGCCUUAUCGGGCUCCAGCCAUCUCAUGAGGGGAGAGGAGACGGAGGGGAGUAGAGAAGUUACACAGAAAUGCUGCUGGCCAAAUAGCAAAGACAACCUGGGAAGGAAAGGUCUUUGUGGGAUAAUCCAUAUGUUUAAUUUAUUCAACUUCAUCAAUCACUUUAUUUUAUUUUUUUUUCUAACUCCUGGAGACUUAUUUUACUGCUUCAUUAGGUUGAAAUACUGCCAUUCUAGGUAGGGUUUUAUUAUCCCAGGGACUACCUCGGCUUUUAAUUUAAAAAAAAAAAAGAAGUGGGUAAGAAAAUGCAAACCUGUUAUAAGUUAUCGGACAGAAAGCUAGGUGCUCUGUCACCCCCAGGAGGCGCUGUGGUACUGGGGCUGCUGCUAUUUAAGCCAAGAACUGAGGUCCUGGUGAGAGCGUUGGACCCAGGCUUGGCUGCCUGACAUAAGCUAAAUCUCCCAGACCCACCACUGGCUACCGAUAUCUAUUUGGUGGGAGGUGUGGCCCUGUUCUUCCUCACCCCAGUUCCAUGACAUUGGCUGGUAUAGGAGCCACAGUCAGGAAAGCACUUGAGGCAGCAUCUGUUGGGCCACCCCCGGCUCAGUGCUGGAAUGUUGCAGUGUAGGUUUCCCAGGGAAGGGGGGUGGGGGUAGGUGGGCUCCACAGGAUGGGGGAGGAGCAUGUCCACUGAGUAUCUUCCUUAUGUUGCUGUGAUAUUGAUAGCUUUUAUUUUCUAAUUUUUAAAAAAUGGUCAUAUUAUGAGUCAAAGAGUAUCAAAUCAGUGUUGGAUGGACCACCCAAGGGUGAGGAGAGGGGCUGGAAGCCCUGGGCAUUAGGAGAAGGGAGUGGGUGCUGGCAUGGACAUGACUGGAUAGAAUUUUCUCAGGAGGGAGCUUGGUGGAUUUUGAAGGUAAAACUUUCUGGGUUUAUCAUGUUUUAAUUUUAGAGACAGGGAGUGAUGAAUCAUCACCGGUUGUCCCCUUAUCUAACUCCAUAAAAGUGGGAAUUUCAAAAGAACACCUCAUCCAAGGAGCUGGGGCAGACUUCAUUGAUUCUAGAGAGACCUGUUUCAGUGCCUACUCAUCCCUGCCCUCUGGUGCCAGCCUCCUUACCAUCACGGCUUCACUGAGGUGUAGGUGGGUUUUUCUUAAACAGGAGACAGUCUCUCCCCUCUUACCUCAACUUCUUGGGGUGGGAAUCAGUGAUACUGGAGAUGGCUAGUUGCUGUGUUACGGGUUUGAGUUACAUUUGGCUAUAAAACAAUCUUGUUGGGAAAAAUGUGGGGGAGAGGACUUCUUCCUACACGCGCAUUGAGACAGAUUCCAACUGGUUAAUGAUAUUGUUUGUAAGAAAGAGAUUCUGUUGGUUGACUGCCUAAAGAGAAAGGUGGGAUGGCCUUCAGAUUAUACCAGCUUAGCUAGCAUUACUAACCAACUGUUGGAAGCUCUGAAAAUAAAAGAUCUUGAACCCAUGCUCUCUGCCUAGUUCUUGAUGGAUUUAAGGA